ACUCUCCAAGAGACUGCUGGCGCCGGCGCCCGCCCGCGCGGCACCGACGCGGGGAGCGCGCUUCGCGCUGACUCAGCGGCGGCGGCGGCUGCGGCGGCGGCGGCGGCGUUAGCCGGCCCUCGCGCUCUUUCCCUUCCUGGGGCGCCGACCCCGCCCGCUUGCUUGCUUGCUUGCUUGCCUGCCUGCCUGCCUGCCCGGCGCCACGCAAGAGAAGGUGCCAGGGGACGCAGAGCGACUAGAGGCGCGCGGUCCCGGCCAGCACCGUCUCUGGCGUUGUAGCUGCGGCCGUGGCGGAGGACUACGGCGACAAGGACGAGGGCCGCUCUCCCAGCUCUCUGCGUGCCGCGCCGCUCCGCUCCGCUGGCUGACCAUCUGGAGUGCAGGCUGGGAGGCGGGAUGGAGUGAUAGGGAAGGUGACUCGGGGCUCGGGGGCAGCGGGACCGGGACCAGGUUUGGUCCGCGUGAGGCUUCGAGGAAGUUGGCCGGGGCGGACCGGCCCGGGGGAGUCCCGACGCCAGGGAGGGUGCAGGCUUGGGACCCUCUAUGGCGGUGCACCCCCUGGCUGGGCGGACCGGGUGGGGGUGGGUACGAGCCGGGGCCGCCGCCGAGGAGCGCGUCCCGAGUGCGUGGCCGGCGGUUGCUUGGUGUUUCAUCACCCGAAUUGCCACGAGGCUUCCUUUAGGGGAGGGAUCGGGGGAGGGAUGGGAGCAAGGCUAGCAGAGGAGGGUCGGCAUCGCCUGUGGUUCCGAAGCCCGUUAGUCAUCGUUGUAGCGUUAUCAACUGUGGAGACCUCAAACUUGAUUCUUCCCCCACCCCUGGACAAAAAGGAAAAGUGUUAUUUCUGUGCAGUAAUUGGCCAGCACGGACGCUCCAUUUCUUCUCAAACCUUCCUCACCAUCCUGCAGGACUAGAGAAGCAUGAGGUUUCCCUGUAACCAGAAAAACGAGUACUUUUUGAAAGUGCUAAUUAGUUGUGGCGGGCGGGGGUUGGGGGAGAGUUACGUUUUAUUAAACCGACUUGUCAGCGUGGUGUUAAAAGGCUGGAAAGAUUCAGUCGUAGUAUUUGAAACAGUCUUCAGUAGGUGUAGAGGAAUUUUUCCAAAUUGUUUGAUUCUUAAUGGCUAUCCAGGAAAAGUUAAGGCUUAAUAUUUUAAGUAUGUUGCUUGCCUUCCCCCAAGAACCUUUGCAAGAUGCAUAAUUGUUUACCGUAUUGAAACAUUUUUUGGGGUUUUGUUGUUGUUGUUUUGAGACGGAGUCUCGCUCGGUCGCCCAGGCUGCAGUGCAGUGGUGCCAUCUCGGCUCACUGCAACCUCUGCCUCCCAGGUUCAAGUGAUUCUGCAGCCUCAGCCUCCCGAGUAGCUCUAUUACAGAUGUUUAUAAAUUCUUCUGUGGGAUCAGAGGGCACGCCUAUUACAACCAGAAAACUACAAGUAUAACAGCGAGGAUGGAUGAACAGGCUCUAUUAGGGCUAAAUCCAAAUGCUGAUUCAGACUUUAGACAAAGGGCCCUGGCCUAUUUUGAGCAGUUAAAAAUUUCCCCAGAUGCCUGGCAGGUGUGUGCAGAAGCUCUAGCCCAGAGGACAUACAGUGAUGAUCAUGUGAAGUUUUUCUGCUUUCAAGUACUGGAACAUCAAGUUAAAUACAAAUACUCAGAACUAACCACUGUUCAACAACAGCUAAUUAGGGAGACGCUCAUAUCAUGGCUGCAAGCUCAGAUGCUGAAUCCCCAACCAGAGAAGACCUUUAUACGAAAUAAAGCCGCCCAAGUCUUCGCCUUGCUUUUUGUUACAGAGUAUCUCACUAAGUGGCCCAAGUUUUUUUUUGACAUUCUCUCAGUAGUGGACCUAAAUCCAAGGGGAGUAGAUCUCUACCUGCGAAUCCUCAUGGCUAUUGAUUCAGAGUUGGUGGAUCGUGAUGUGGUGCAUACAUCAGAGGAGGCUCGUAGGAAUACUCUCAUAAAAGAUACCAUGAGGGAACAGUGCAUUCCAAAUCUGGUGGAAUCAUGGUACCAAAUAUUACAAAAUUAUCAGUUUACUAAUUCUGAAGUGACGUGUCAGUGCCUUGAAGUAGUUGGGGCUUAUGUCUCUUGGAUAGACUUAUCCCUUAUAGCCAAUGAUAGGUUUAUAAAUAUGCUGCUAGGUCAUAUGUCAAUAGAAGUUCUACGGGAAGAAGCAUGUGACUGUUUAUUUGAAGUUGUAAAUAAAGGAAUGGACCCUGUUGAUAAAAUGAAACUAGUGGAAUCUUUGUGUCAAGUAUUACAGUCUGCUGGGUUUUUCAGCAUUGACCAGGAAGAAGAUGUUGACUUCCUGGCCAGAUUUUCUAAGUUGGUAAAUGGAAUGGGACAGUCAUUGAUAGUUAGUUGGAGUAAAUUAAUUAAGAAUGGGGAUAUUAAGAAUGCUCAAGAGGCACUACAAGCUAUUGAAACAAAAGUGGCACUGAUGUUGCAGCUACUAAUUCAUGAGGAUGAUGAUAUUUCUUCUAAUAUUAUUGGAUUUUGUUACGAUUAUCUUCAUAUUUUGAAACAGCUUACAGUGCUCUCGGAUCAGCAAAAAGCUAAUGUAGAGGCAAUCAUGUUGGCCGUUAUGAAAAAAUUGACUUACGAUGAAGAAUAUAACUUUGAAAAUGAGGGUGAAGAUGAAGCCAUGUUUGUAGAAUAUAGAAAACAACUGAAGUUACUGUUGGACAGGCUUGCUCAAGUUUCACCAGAGUUACUACUGGCCUCUGUUCGCAGAGUUUUUAGUUCUACACUGCAGAAUUGGCAGACUACACGGUUUAUGGAAGUUGAAGUAGCAAUAAGAUUGCUGUAUAUGUUGGCAGAAGCUCUUCCAGUAUCUCAUGGUGCUCACUUCUCAGGUGAUGUUUCAAAAGCUAGUGCUUUGCAGGAUAUGAUGCGAACUCUGGUAACAUCAGGAGUCAGUUCCUAUCAGCAUACAUCUGUGACAUUGGAGUUCUUCGAAACUGUUGUUAGAUAUGAAAAGUUUUUCACAGUUGAACCUCAGCACAUUCCAUGUGUACUAAUGGCUUUCUUAGAUCACAGAGGUCUGCGGCAUUCCAGUGCAAAAGUUCGGAGCAGGACGGCUUACCUGUUUUCUAGAUUUGUCAAAUCUCUCAAUAAGCAAAUGAAUCCUUUCAUUGAGGAUAUUUUGAAUAGAAUACAAGAUUUAUUAGAGCUUUCUCCACCUGAGAAUGGCCACCAGUCCUUACUGAGCAGCGAUGAUCAACUUUUUAUUUAUGAGACAGCUGGAGUGCUGAUUGUUAAUAGUGAAUAUCCGGCAGAAAGGAAACAAGCCUUAAUGAGGAAUCUGUUGACUCCACUAAUGGAGAAGUUUAAAAUUCUGUUAGAAAAGUUGAUGCUGGCACAAGAUGAAGAAAGGCAAGCCUCUCUAGCAGACUGUCUUAACCAUGCUGUUGGAUUUGCAAGUCGAACCAGUAAAGCUUUCAGCAACAAACAGACUGUGAAACAAUGUGGCUGUUCCGAAGUUUAUCUGGACUGUUUACAGACAUUCUUGCCAGCCCUCAGUUGUCCCUUACAAAAGGAUAUUCUCAGAAGUGGAGUCCGUACUUUCCUUCAUCGAAUGAUUAUUUGCCUGGAGGAAGAAGUUCUUCCGUUCAUUCCAUCUGCUUCAGAACAUAUGCUCAAAGAUUGUGAAGCAAAAGAUCUCCAGGAGUUCAUUCCUCUUAUCAACCAGAUUACGGCCAAAUUCAAGAUACAGGUAUCCCCGUUUUUACAACAGAUGUUCAUGCCCCUGCUUCAUGCAAUUUUUGAAGUGCUGCUCCGGCCAGCAGAAGAAAAUGACCAGUCUGCUGCUUUAGAGAAGCAGAUGUUGCGGAGGAGUUACUUUGCUUUCCUGCAAACAGUCACAGGCAGUGGGAUGAGCGAAGUUAUAGCAAAUCAAGGUGCAGAGAAUGUAGAAAGAGUGUUGGUUACUGUUAUCCAAGGAGCAGUUGAAUAUCCAGAUCCAAUUGCACAGAAAACAUGUUUUAUCAUCCUCUCAAAGUUGGUAGAACUCUGGGGAGGUAAAGAUGGACCAGUGGGAUUUGCUGAUUUUGUUUAUAAGCACAUUGUCCCCGCAUGUUUCCUAGCACCUUUAAAACAAACCUUUGACCUGGCAGAUGCACAAACAGUAUUGGCUUUAUCUGAGUGUGCAGUGACACUGAAAACAAUUCAUCUCAAACGGGGCCCAGAAUGUGUUCAGUAUCUUCAACAAGAAUACCUGCCCUCCUUGCAAGUAGCUCCAGAAAUAAUUCAGGAGUUUUGUCAAGCGCUUCAGCAGCCUGAUGCUAAAGUUUUUAAAAAUUACUUAAAGGUGUUCUUCCAGAGAGCAAAGCCCUGAGGACUGGAUUUCCCUGUGCCUACUUCAUGAUCAUGAAUUCCAGUUAAUUUAUAAAGAGGCGAUUUUUGUGUGCCAUUCACACUGGUCUUUUUCACAUUGUUUUGAGCUUAUUGCAGUAUAUGUUUUGGGAUUUUUCUGUAAAAUGGGUGUAAUUUUCCUAAUACAGGUAUGUAACAACAAAAGAAGUUGCCUGCAUGCCGGUCCAAAUUGUUCUGUAUAAAGAUGCUCUUAAAAGACACAAGAGUUAUCCUAGAACCUUAAUUCUUUUUUAUUUGAAAUUUUAAGUCAAGUCCUUUAUAAAGACCAUAGCAGUGGAAAACAGUGUACUUUUUAAAAAAUUGCUGAAUAUAAAAUCUUUGAAAAUUUUCUUUAUGUGUGAAGACACAAAGUAUGGGGGAAGACAGCAAUCAAAACUAACUUUUUGUAGAUAGCCAUUUCAUUUCUUUAAACUGUUUCAACGCCAAUAUGUAUUCUACAAAAGAGAAUGGUUUUAGGCUCCAGUGUUAUACUUUUUUUUAUAUAUAUAUAUAAAAAUAAACUUUACGUAGUGAAAUCUUCCAAGUCUUUUCUGGAAUUAUUAUAAAUACUUUAGUUUUAUUUUCUCAUCUUAAUCUCUCCAUAAUUUCCCAUUUAAAGGUUUACAAAUAUGAGUGUGUGGAUGCUUUAAUUCAUUUAACCUCACUCCUCAAAGGUAACAUGCAACUUAGUUCUGUUAUAUGAGAGUCUUUUUCUUUAAUGUACUGGAAAAAGCCUAUGUGAAUCUGUUGAUAGAAUUUAAAAUUCCAGGCCGGGCGUGGUGGCUCACGACUGUAAUCCCAGAACUUUGGGAGGCCAAGGCAGGUGGAUCACUUGAGGUCAGGAGUUCGAGACUAGCCUGGCCAACAUGGUGAAACCCCAUCUCUACUAAAAAUACAACAGCCAGGUGUGAUGGUGCACGCUCGUAAUCCCGGCUACUCAGGAGGCUGAGGCAGGAGAAUCGCUUGAACCCGGAAGGCAGAGGUUGCAGUGAGCUGAGAUUGUGCCACUGCACGCCAGCCUGGGCAAGAGAGUAAGACUCUCUCUCAAAAAAAAAAAAAAAGAAUUUAAAAUCCCAAUUUAUUUUCUAACUCUUUUAUUGGAUGUAUUUAGAACACAGUAUACCUAUAGUAUACCUAUGUGUUUAUUAUGUUUGUAAAUGGUAACUGACAUUUAAUUAUUAGAAGUACUUACCCCUGCCUUCCUCCAUUUUUAUUCAUGGCUACUUGAGAAAGCAAAAGGAAAAAAUAAUAGUUAUCAGUAGUGUCACUGGAAAGAAGAGAGGAGGGACAAAACUGAGCAGCAGAAUUCGUAUAGACAUUUACGUUUAAAUUCUAAAAGCCCAAUUGAGAUGUUCAGGGAGGGUUUGUUUUGCCCUUUGGCCUCAUGAAUGGGUUUCAUGAAUGGGCUUCAGUGGCUUAUAAACUCUGUAAAAUUCUAUUCUAAAUUUUGUACAUUUAUUUUGUUCCGGUUAAUUCCAGAAGACAUUUCAAACAUUUUUCUUACACCAUAUAAUAAAAAUACUUAACUAAAUUGACAGUUAUAAAAAUAAAUCAGUGAAAUGUACCUUAUACUUUAAUAAAAAAUGUUUUCAGAAAUAGAUAAGUGAAAGCUGAGUGUUUCUUUGAUAGGUUCCCCUGUACUAUAGGAGUGAUAAUUGCAGCUAUUGCAAUAGUAGUAAUUGUUAAAUGGAUACUAAUGAAUAGCAUAGCAUAGUGGGUAAGAGUUUAUAUAGCACAGGCUCUAGAAUCAGAUUAAGUAGGUUCAAAUACCAGUUCUGCCAGUAACUGGUUUUAGAACCUUGGGCAAGUUAAAGAAUGUCUCCCAGCCUCAGUUUCCCUAUUUGUAAAAUGGAAAUAAUGGUAGCUACCUCAAACCUCAUUACGAAUUCAAUGAGUUAAACUUGAAAAGACUUAUUACAGUAGCUGGCACAUAAAGACUUGAUAGUAGUUUAUAUGGAUGCUAUCUCAUAUUAGCAUAUAUGGAAUUAAUAGUGUAUCACUAUACUUUUUUUUUCUUUUUUUUUUUUGAAUAGAGAUCAGUCUAUCACCCAGGCUGGAGUGCAGUGGUGACAUCAUAGCUCACUGUAACUUCUCCCAUACUCUACCAAUCCUCCUGCCUCAGCAUCCAGACUAGCUGUGAUUACAGGUGUGCACCACCACACCCAGCUACAUUUUUUUUUGGUAGAGACAGGGUCUCACUAUGUUACCCAGUCUGGUCUCAAACUCCCGGCCUCAAGCAAUCCUCCCACUGGCCUCACAAUGUUGGGAUUACAGGUAUAAGCCACUGCACACGGCCUUACUAUGCUAUCAAUUCCAUAUAUGGAAAGGUGUUUUCCCUUUCAGAGCUCUUUAAAGCUCUGCAGAAGAUUUACAUGUGUUUAUAGAGCUAAGAGAAAUCAGGGCAUGGAAAUUGAGUGUGUAAUAAAAAUUAAACUCUUCAUGUUAUAUAAUCAUGCAUAACUUCUAUCUUCAUUCUCUGAAGUUGCCUAGAGCACCAUCACAGCUAGGAAGCUUCCAUCAUGAAUUACCUUAUUUCCAAAAGCAAGUACUCAAAUAAUUGUCUCAAGAGAGGAAGGACAAAACUGUUACAAGCUGAAAUAUUUGGGGAUUUGUUUGACUUGACUAGGGAACCACAAGUUUUCAUAUAAUGCCUGAUUUAGCCCUGUGCCUAACAGUUUAAAUCUUAAUGCUAAUGUUAAUUGCUUCCCAGUUGGUUGACCUUAUAAGAAAACACUGUGUGGUAUUUUAAUGUGGUAAACAUGUGAAUGAAGGCCUGUGGCUCAGUUAAUCACUCCCACAACUUUGAGCUGUGAGUUUUACUGGUGGAAGGAACUUUAACAGGUCUUCGCUCUUGUCAUUAGAUAUCAAAGAACUGAAAUUAGUUGGAAUUGUAAGCAGUGAAUAGAUGUGUUGUUAGAAUGAUUCCAUCACUUAUACAUUGUUUAAAAUGCUAAUAAAGUAACUUGCUUUGUAAGAA